AGUCAUACUGCACCAGCUGAGCAAUGCAUGGAGUGGACCUGUAGGCGACUUGCAUCGUCUUCAACAUGAAGAUAGCCACAGUGUCAGUGCUUCUGCCCUUGGCUCUUUGCCUCAUACAAGAUGCUGCCAGUAAGAAUGAAGAUCAGGAAAUGUGCCAUGAAUUUCAGGCAUUUAUGAAAAAUGGAAAACUGUUCUGUCCCCAGGAUAAGAAAUUUUUUCAAAGUCUUGAUGGAAUAAUGUUCAUCAAUAAAUGUGCCACGUGCAAAAUGAUACUGGAAAAAGAAGCAAAAUCACAGAAGAGGGCCAGGCAUUUAGCAAGAGCUCCCAAGGCUACUGCCCCAACAGAGCUGAAUUGUGAUGAUUUUAAAAAAGGAGAAAGAGAUGGGGAUUUUAUCUGUCCUGAUUAUUAUGAAGCUGUUUGUGGCACAGAUGGGAAAACAUAUGACAACAGAUGUGCACUGUGUGCUGAGAAUGCGAAAACCGGGUCCCAAAUUGGUGUAAAAAGUGAAGGGGAAUGUAAGAGCAGUAAUCCAGAGCAGGAUGUAUGCAGUGCUUUUCGGCCCUUUGUUAGAGAUGGAAGACUUGGAUGCACAAGGGAAAAUGAUCCUGUUCUUGGUCCUGAUGGGAAGACGCAUGGCAAUAAGUGUGCAAUGUGUGCUGAGCUGUUUUUAAAAGAAGCUGAAAAUGCCAAGCGAGAGGGUGAAACUAGAAUUCGACGAAAUGCUGAAAAGGAUUUUUGCAAGGAAUAUGAAAAACAAGUGAGAAAUGGAAGGCUUUUUUGUACACGGGAGAGUGAUCCAGUCCGUGGCCCUGACGGCAGGAUGCAUGGCAACAAAUGUGCCCUGUGUGCUGAAAUUUUCAAGCAGCGUUUUUCAGAGGAAAACAGUAAAACAGAUCAAAAUUUGGGAAAAGCUGAAGAAAAAACUAAAGUUAAAAGAGAAAUUGUGAAACUCUGCAGUCAAUAUCAAAAUCAGGCAAAGAAUGGAAUACUUUUCUGUACCAGAGAAAAUGACCCUAUUCGUGGUCCAGAUGGGAAAAUGCAUGGCAACUUGUGUUCCAUGUGUCAAGCCUACUUCCAAGCAGAAAAUGAAGAAAAGAAAAAGGCUGAAGCACGAGCUAGAAACAAAAGAGAAUCUGGAAAAGCAACCUCAUAUGCAGAGCUUUGCAGUGAAUAUCGAAAGCUUGUGAGGAACGGAAAACUUGCUUGCACCAGAGAGAACGAUCCUAUCCAGGGCCCAGAUGGGAAAGUGCAUGGCAACACCUGCUCCAUGUGUGAGGUCUUCUUCCAAGCAGAAGAAGAAGAAAAGAAAAAGAAGGAAGGUAAAUCAAGAAACAAAAGACAAUCUAAGAGUACAGCUUCCUUUGAGGAGUUGUGUAGUGAAUACCGCAAAUCCAGGAAAAACGGACGGCUUUUUUGCACCAGAGAGAAUGACCCCAUCCAGGGCCCAGAUGGAAAAAUGCAUGGCAACACCUGCUCCAUGUGUGAGGCCUUCUUUCAACAAGAAGAAAGAGCAAGAGCAAAGGCUAAAAGAGAAGCUGCAAAGGAAAUCUGCAGUGAAUUUCGGGACCAAGUGAGGAAUGGAACACUUAUAUGCACCAGGGAGCAUAAUCCUGUCCGUGGCCCAGAUGGCAAAAUGCAUGGAAACAAGUGUGCCAUGUGUGCCAGUGUGUUCAAACUUGAAGAAGAAGAGAAGAAAAAUGAUAAAGAAGAAAAAGGGAAAGUCGAGGCUGAAAAAGUUAAGAGAGAAGCAGUUCAGGAGCUGUGCAGUGAAUAUCGUCAUUAUGUGAGGAAUGGACGACUCCCCUGUACCAGAGAGAAUGAUCCUAUUGAGGGUCUAGAUGGGAAAAUCCACGGCAACACCUGCUCCAUGUGUGAAGCCUUCUUCCAGCAAGAAGCAAAAGAAAAAGAAAGAGCUGAACCCAGAGCAAAAGUCAAAAGAGAAGCUGAAAAGGAGACAUGCGAUGAAUUUCGGAGACUUUUGCAAAAUGGAAAACUUUUCUGCACAAGAGAAAAUGAUCCUGUGCGUGGCCCAGAUGGCAAGACCCAUGGCAACAAGUGUGCCAUGUGUAAGGCAGUCUUCCAGAAAGAAAAUGAGGAAAGAAAGAGGAAAGAAGAGGAAGAUCAGAGAAAUGCUGCAGGACAUGGUUCCAGUGGUGGUGGAGGAGGAAACACUCAGGACGAAUGUGCUGAGUAUCGGGAACAAAUGAAAAAUGGAAGACUCAGCUGUACUCGGGAGAGUGAUCCUGUACGUGAUGCUGAUGGCAAAUCGUACAACAAUCAGUGUACCAUGUGUAAAGCAAAAUUGGAAAGAGAAGCAGAGAGAAAAAAUGAGUAUUCUCGCUCCAGAUCAAAUGGGACUGGAUCAGAAUCAGGGAAGGAUACAUGUGAUGAGUUUAGAAGCCAAAUGAAAAAUGGAAAACUCAUCUGCACUCGAGAAAGUGACCCUGUCCGGGGUCCAGAUGGCAAGACACAUGGCAAUAAGUGUACUAUGUGUAAGGAAAAACUGGAAAGGGAAGCAGCUGAAAAAAAAAAGAAAGAGGAUGAAGACAGGAGCAAUACAGGAGAAAGGAGCAAUACAGGAGAAAGGAGCAAUGACAAAGAGGAUCUGUGUCGUGAAUUUCGAAGCAUGCAGAGAAAUGGAAAGCUUAUCUGCACCAGAGAAAAUAACCCUGUUCGAGGCCCAUAUGGCAAGAUGCACAUCAAUAAAUGUGCUAUGUGUCAGAGCAUCUUUGAUCGAGAAGCUAAUGAAAGAAAAAAGAAAGAUGAAGAGAAAUCAAGUAGCAAGCCCUCAAAUAAUGCAAAGGACCAGUGCAGACAGGUUCAGAAUGAAGCGGAGGAUGCAAAAUUUAGACAACCUGGGCGUUCCUUGGCCUCUGUUGCCAGGAUGAGUACAGAUGAGUGCAGUGAAUUUCGAAACUAUAUAAGGAACAAUGAACUCAUCUGCCCUAGAGAGAAUGACCCAGUGCACGGUGCUGAUGGAAAGUUCUAUACAAACAAGUGCUACAUGUGCAGAGCUGUCUUUCUAACAGAAGCUUUGGAAAGGGCAAAGCUUCAAGAAAAGCCAUCCCAUGUUAGAGCUUCUCAAGAGGAAGACAGCCCAGACUCUUUCAGUUCUCUGGAUUCUGAGAUGUGCAAAGACUACCGAGUAUUGCCCAGGAUAGGUUAUCUUUGUCCAAAGGAUUUAAAGCCUGUCUGUGGUGACGAUGGCCAAACCUACAACAAUCCUUGCAUGCUCUGUCAUGAAAACCUGAUACGCCAAACAAAUACACACAUCCGCAGUACAGGGAAGUGUGAGGAGAGCAGCACCCCAGGAACCACCGCAGCCAGCAUGCCCCCGUCUGACGAAUGACAGGAAGAUUGUUGAAAGCCAUGAGGGAAAAAAUAAACCCCAGUUCUGAAUCACCUACCUUCACCAUCUGUAUAUACAAAGAAUUCUUCGGAGCUUGUCUUAUUUGCUAUAGAAAACAAUACAGAGCUUUUGGGAAUGGACUCACUGAUUUUCAGUCUUUUCCAUCUCUUUCCUCCUAGACUCUGUGAUCUGAGGGUAUAAAGACAUCUCCACCAAGUCUGAGCCCUCAAAAUGUCCUGAUUACAAUGCUGUCUGUCCAACUGCCUGUUCAAUAAAAGUAAACUCAGCAGAACACCCUUUCUGGGAUUUCUUUGUCACUAUCUGGAUAAUAGAUAUUUGCUUUUAAAGAAACUGAAUAAACUCUACCCUUUUGUCUUUUUGUGUUGCUAAA